AGCAGCAGCUGCAGCGGCAGCAGCGGCAGCAGAGGCAGCAGCAGUAGCCACCACUCCGCCGAGGCCGCAACCCCGGCUCGGCCUCCCCAGGCCCCGCCGCUGCCGCAGUCAUGGCUGCUGAUGGGGUGGACGAACGCUCGCCUCUGCUGUCAGCAUCCCACUCCGGAAAUGUCACUCCCACCGCCCCACCGUACUUGCAAGAAAGCAGCCCCAGAGCGGAGCUCCCACCUCCAUAUACAGCCAUUGCCAGUCCAGACGCCAGUGGUAUUCCAGUAAUAAACUGCCGUGUGUGCCAAUCACUAAUCAAUUUGGAUGGCAAGCUUCACCAGCAUGUGGUUAAGUGCACAGUUUGCAAUGAAGCUACGCCAAUCAAAAACCCCCCAACAGGCAAGAAAUAUGUUAGAUGCCCUUGUAAUUGUCUUCUCAUUUGUAAGGACACAUCUCGGCGAAUAGGAUGCCCAAGACCCAACUGUAGACGGAUAAUUAACCUUGGCCCAGUAAUGCUUAUUUCUGAAGAACAACCAGCUCAGCCUGCAUUGCCAAUCCAACCAGAAGGUACAAGGGUCGUGUGUGGGCACUGUGGAAACACAUUCCUGUGGAUGGAACUGAGGUUCAACACUCUGGCAAAAUGCCCACACUGCAAAAAAAUCUCCUCAGUGGGUAGUGCACUUCCACGAAGACGCUGCUGUGCAUAUAUUACCAUUGGAAUGAUAUGUAUUUUCAUUGGAGUUGGGUUAACUGUUGGCACCCCAGAUUUUGCAAGGCGAUUUCGAGCAACCUAUGUUUCUUGGGCAAUUGCUUAUCUCCUAGGAUUGAUCUGCCUUAUCCGAGCUUGUUAUUGGGGAGCCAUAAGAGUCAGUUAUCCAGAACACAGUUUUGCAUAAGCUUGUUUAUGAUUCAGUAAUGCAGGUGAGAGUGUCUAGCAGUUCUUGGUAAGCUACUCUGGACAUCUUUAAAUUAUUUAUCCUAAUGGAUUCCAUUCUGGUUUAUGUAUAAUCGUUUCAAGACUUUGGGAGUCUUUUAUGAACAAAUGCUCAUUGCACUAUAUUAUAUGCAAAUUGUUUUGCUGCUAGGUUUUCAAAAUUUGAAUAAUAAAGCCUUUUCAUGUUCUUUUACAUCUCUUAUAGAUAUUUUUGGAUUUGUUACCAAACAUUACAUUUACUCUCACCCUUUUAUUAUUUUUAAAUAAGUUAUUUCAUUACUUGCUGAUACAUGAGUAUUCCUAAGUGUUUAUAAAUAUUUCUAUAAUAGUUUCACAUUUAUAUUUACAUUUUAAUUAAACAGUAUCAAAAUUGCUUGCUUAAAACCUAAGCAAUAUGCAUUUUGCUUGAACUGCUUACUGUAACUUUAACCUAAGAUUAUAGUGACCUUAUUCAGGAAAAAAAAAAAAAUUUAGUGUAACUUCAAAGACUUGACAUUCUUGUCAGAGGAAAAAAAAUUUCUAGAUACUGUUUGCUUGUUUUUUGUUGUUUGUAGAAAGAUAAAAUAUUUUGGUAGUAAUUUAAAAUACAAGAACGAAUAUUUAUUUGUCCACAGUUGGAGAUGUUGGAUAAAUGUCUUUUCUCAAAGAUCACAGGACUUUUGUCUUUCAUUUUUGCCUUUUUAUUUACCAUUUAUAAAAGAUCUGGUCUGGAUUAUGGAAUUUAAUGUUUAUCAGCUCUAUGUAUUCCUUUAUAGAGGCUUGAGGAAGUAUUUCACAUAACAUGUUUUAUAAUACUUAACCAUUUAUCCAAAGAUAUAUUUACAUUGGGUUGUGCCCCUUUCCCUUAGAUCAUGGUAAAUUUUUCUUAUUGAGGUAAUUAUGUACUACUUAUAUUUGAAGGAAGCUUAUGACAUUUUACAGUAGCUAAAAUGUUGAGAUUAGAGGUACUUUUACUAUUCUUCUCAAAGGUAACUGAUCAGAUAAUUACCCAAAUUAUUCAAGAAAAUAGAUCAGAAAUAAAGAACAACAUAAUUUUCUAAGAAUUCAUUGAAAUUUAUGGAAUCAGCUCUCGCACUGCCCAUCUUUGCAGUUUUGAAAAAGAAAUUGCUUAAUCACAAAUGUUCUACAGUCUUUAAAUGUAGUAGAAUUAGACAGUGAGAUCAUCUGAGUAAAUUGAUUGGUGAUUCCAGAGAUAAGACUAAUAUUUUAAAUUAUUUAUGAUACUGAUUAGUAUAAAAACGUACUCAUCACAGAAUUUGAAGCAAAAUACAUGUACACUUCAAAGAGUAAAUGACAAAUGUAUAAAUGCUGUAGCUCAGGAUUAUAUGUACCUUUAAAAAUACACUAAUAAAGAUUAUUGUUCAAAAAUUACCUUGUUUUAUUCCAUUAAAAAUAAUGUCACUUCCAGAGUUGCCUUGAAAUCUUGCUGUAAAGUUUUCAUGUUUAGGAAUGUACCUGUUUCUUUAUAUAAUAUUCAUUUAUGUUUUUUGUACUAUUUUCAAAUGGUUUUAUUUUUAAAAUAUAGUUUUUAAAUCCAUUUGUAAUACACUUGAUGUUAGGUAUAAAAUAAUCUUACUUCUUUUCCUAAUGGUUAACUAGUUGUAACAGCAUUGUAUACUGAAUAAUCCAUUCUUUCCCUCAUUGAUUGGAAAGCUCACAUUAAAUUAUAUGCUAUGUCAUAUUCCUUCUGGAAUAAUAACUUUAUGAGAGCAAGAACCCUGGUAGUCUUGUUCACAGCUUUAUCCCCACUUAGAACAGUUCUUAGUGUACAUGUGCUCAAUUUACGUGAAUGAAUAUGCAUGAAUGAAUAAAUGGUUGAAUGAAUUGCUAUUUUAAA